AGCCUUGCCUUCGCCGCCGUUGGGGCUGGAAGUUCCCGCCAGGUCCGUGCCGGGCGAGAGAGAUGCUGCCCGGCCCGCCUCGGCUUUGAGGCGAGAGAAGUGUCCCAGACCCAUUUCGCCUUGCUGACGGCGUCGAGCCCUGGCCAGACAUGUCCACAGGGUUCUCCUUCGGGUCCGGGACUCUGGGCUCCACCACCGUGGCCGCCGGCGGGACCAGCACAGGCGGCGUUUUCUCCUUCGGAACGGGAGCGUCUAGGUAACCGCACUUUCUCGCCUUCCUGGGCCGGAUUCACCCCCACCCCCACCCCCGCAAAGCUCCCUUGGUGUCCCCAUCCUGUCUCUUCCCUCUGGCUUCCUUCCCAGUGGGGCUGGAGAGAAGCACUUAAUCUAGCCGCCCGGCGUCGUAGGCCUCUCGCCGCGGUACCCGGGCCCAGCGCGGCCUGGUGAAGUGGAGGGCGGGAUGGGUUCUGUGCUGUGAGGUUUCCAGAAUCCACGUAUAGUUCAGGCAUUAUUUGGACCUAGUGGGGUCUUGACUGCGUGGAAGGGCCUUGGGGUCUACCCCGGAGCUUUAGCGAUGUGUCAGUCUUAGGCAUAGAAUGAACAUUGAAUGAAUGAAUGAAAUUAUAGCAUACUGUGGAGUUUUAUGAUAGAUAAUUCCGAUUUCAUUGCAGCAUUUGCGGUUUUGGAUAUGACGGUGUUUUAAUAACUUUGUGGUUUUUAACCAGCUUUUCAAGCUUUUGUGCCACAUGGGACCUUAUCUGUUUUUGUUAAAAAAAACAAAAACACUUUUUUACAGUGUUUAUUAGUGGUAAUUUUCUGCAGUAUGUGCAGAUUAGUAUAUCUGAUGCGAGAAUGUUGUGUUGUAAUAACUCAAUUUGUCUUUUACUUAAAUUACAAAACGUAGGUAGCAUGUUCCUUGUUUUUGUGCAACCCAUUAGUUCAGGUGGCGACAAAAACAUAACUAUCCAGAAAGAAACAAAGUGGUGAGACAUUUUAAUGAGAGAUUUAAGCUUUAGAACUCAAUUUUUUUUAAGAUAAAGGUGGAGGGGUUCAUAAAGUUAAGGAGUGUGCACACUGUCAACAAGAUACUUCCUGAAGCUUAAAAGAUGUGGCUGUAGAUUUAAAAGGCAAAUACUUAAGCAUGACCUGCAGUUUAAAAAGGGAGGGAGGAGGAACCACGGACUACACAGUCAAUUCAGAAAUUUGAAUUUUCAUCCAUACCUCCGUUAUUCUUACUCUACUCGCUCAACAACAGGUUCUGAUAAUGUUACUUCUGCCAUUUCUGUUUGUCUUUAUUUCCAGUUCCACAACCCUGCUUAGGCUAUUGUCAUUCGUGGAACAAAUAUUUAUUGGACAGAUUCCCAUGUGCAAGGCUCUGUUUUAGAUGAAAACUACUCCAAUCAACUUCUUCAAUCUGUUCUGCCACAUUUUAGCCAGAGAAGAACAGAAACAUAUUUGAACUUGAUGGGUUAAAGCAACCCUUCUGUGGGGCUCAAUUUUGGAAAUCUUGGAAGUACUUCAACUCCAGCAACUACAUCUGCUCCUUCAAGUGGUUUUGGAACCGGGCUCUUUGGAUCUAAACCUGCCACUGGGUUCACUCUAGGAGGAACAAAUACAGGAAUAGCAACAACUAUAACUACAGGAUUAACUCUGGGAACGCCAGCCACUACAUCUGCAGCUACAACAGGCUUCAGUUUAGGAUUCAAUAAACCUGCAGCAUCUGCCACACCAUUUGCUCUACCUAUUACCUCUACCUCAGCUAGCGGUCUGACUCUUUCGUCUGCUCUGACAUCAACUCCAGCAGCAUCCACAGGAUUUACUCUAAAUAAUUUGGGUGGGACAACAGCCACAACUACAACUGCAUCAACAGGCCUCUCUUUAGGGGGAGCCUUAGCUGGUUUGGGAGGUUCACUUUUCCAGAGUACAAACACAGGAACAUCAGGACUUGGACAGAAUGCUUUAGGGUUGACUUUGGGAACUACAGCAGCUACUUCAACUGCAGGCAAUGAAGGCCUUGGUGGUAUAGAUUUCAGUAGCUCCUCAGAUAAAAAGAGUGAUAAAACGGGAACAAGACCAGAGGAUAGUAAAGCUCUGAAGGAUGAAAAUCUACCUCCUGUCAUCUGCCAGGAUGUUGAAAAUCUCCAGAAAUUUGUGAAGGAGCAGAAACAAGUUCAAGAAGAAAUUAGUAGAAUGUCUUCAAAAGCAAUGCUUAAGGUACAAGAAGAUAUUAAAGCUCUGAAGCAGCUCCUGUCGUUGGCUGCCAAUGGAAUACAGAGAAACACUCUCAACAUUGACAAAUUGAAAAUAGAAACUGCUCAGGAGUUGAAGAAUGCUGAAAUAGCUUUAAGAACCCAGAAGACACCACCUGGACUUCAACAUGAAUAUGCAGCUCCUGCUGACUACUUCAGAAUCUUGGUUCAGCAAUUUGAGGUACAGCUUCAGCAGUACAGGCAGCAGAUUGAAGAACUAGAAAACCAUCUUGCCACUCAAGCAAAUAAUUCACAUAUAACCCCUCAAGAUUUGUCAAUGGCUAUGCAGAAAAUUUAUCAAACAUUUGUAGCUUUAGCGGCACAACUUCAGUCUAUUCAUGAAAAUGUAAAGGUUCUGAAAGAACAGUACCUUGGCUACAGGAAAAUGUUCUUGGGAGAUGCUGUUGAUGUGUUUGAAACAAGGCGAGCAGAAGCCAAGAAGUGGCAGAACACACCCAGAGUUACUACUGGACCCACUCCUUUCAGCACCAUGCCAAACGCAGCAGCCGUUGCCAUGGCUGCAACACUUACACAGCAGCAACAGCCUGCUACAGGGCCACAGCCAUCUCUGGGAGUUAGUUUUGGAACGCCAUUCGGCUCAGGUAUUGGCACUGGCUUGCAAUCAAGUGGCUUAGGUUCUUCAAACCUUGGAGGAUUUGGAACUAGCUCUGGUUUUGGAUGCAGCACCACAGGGGCCUCCACAUUUGGAUUUGGAACAACAAAUAAACCCUCAGGAAGUCUUAGUGCAGGCUUUGGCAGCUCAAGUACAUCUGGGUUUAACUUCAGCAAUCCUGGCAUCACGGCAUCAGCUGGUUUGACUUUUGGGGUGUCCAAUCCUGCCUCUGCAGGUUUUGGAACAGGAGGACAACUCCUUCAGUUGAAGAAACCUCCAGCUGGAAACAAAAGAGGAAAAAGAUAAACAUGGGUUGAUGUGUUGAGAGAAUCCAUAGCAGCACCGUUCAUUCUAUGAGUCUAUUUUUCUAAUGAUGCAGUAAUUAAAUUGCAUCCCAGGAGAUUUAUAAAGUUUUGAUAUUUUUCCCUACUCUGGAAUUUGAACUUUCUUCAUGUUUGCCAUACUGAACAUCUUUUUUCUUGUGGAAUUUAAAGUCCAGCUGUGUUUUCUUUUUAAUUUGAUUCUCAGUGUAAGAAAUGUUCUGAUUACAUCACUGAUUGGUAAUGGUUAGAAACCAUUAACCUAAAACUUACUAUUUAACCUAGUGUUUUUGUUGAUGAGGUUUACAUUAUGUGAAUACAUGCACAUUUGUUUCUUAUACAGGUGGUGUGAACUCUAGGGCCUAUACUAGAAUCAAUUUGUUCCUUGUUAAAGGCCUUUUGAAUUAUACUGCAGGGCAUCUUGUGAAUAUGUAUGUAAAUAUAUACAGAAUAAUACACACAGUUGUGUGUGCAUAUAAAAUACAUAUUUACGCCAGGCGUGGUGGCUCACGCCUGUAAUCCCAGCACUUUGGGAGGCCGAGGCAGGCGGAUCACCUGAGGUCAGGAGUUUGAGACCAGCCUGACAUGGUGAAACCCCAUCUCUACGAAAAAUACAAAAAUUAGCUGGGCAUAGUGGCGGGUACCUAUAAUCCCAGCUACUCGGGAGGCUGAGGCACGAGAAUCACUUGAAGCCGGGAGGUGGGGGUUGCAGUGAGCCGAGAUCACACCACUGCACUCCAGCCUGGGCAACAAGAGCAAAACUCCGUCUCAAAAAAGAUGAAAAUAAAAUAAAAUAUAUAUUUACAGGCCUACAACUUUUGCCUCAGACUGUUCCCCUUUUCUAAGGGUAUUCAAGUUUUCACCUUUUAAGCUUCAUAUCCUCAGUGCUUGUAGAAUGAUGAGCUUAGAGGUACCAGGUCAUUGCAGUUGUUUGCUUAAAGACUUAUUGAAAUGGUUACUGGCGUAAAUACUUGGCCAACUCAACUUUAUUGCCCCUGAUCUUUUCCAUUUUUGUUUCCACCUUAACCUAUAGCAGCUCCUCCAAAUGAGGAAUGCUGUAAGUAAGACUCAUCAAACAGAUUUUAACCAUUUUAUUAUCCUGUGUGUCCUUACAUUGCUUCUGUGAGAUGUUUUUUUCUUAUCUGAGAUGAACUUUCAGGAGCCUAUUUGAACUCCAGACUGGUGUUCUGGGGCAAAGAGCUAUUAGCCAAACUGAUUCUAUGCAGGUGAAGGAUGCACUAAAGUUCUCACUUUAGUGAGAACUUUUCUAGCUAUUCCAAUACAGAGUUCUUUCUUAUAGGGCUAUUGAUAUUGACACCAAAUGGAGUGGCUUCUCAGCCUCUUAAUGUCUUAAGUAAGUGCUUAAUUUGGAAUAGAGAAACCAGUAUAUUUUAAAAAAGAAAAAUAUUCUUUGUAGCAACUGUAAAUUCUCCCAUUAUAACAGUGAACAGAGCUCCAGGUAAUAACGCAUAGGCAUGUCAGGUUGCAUCUGUAUAUUUGACUACAUUAGUAUUAGUGACAUCAGGUGGAUAUAAAAGAAAACCCUUGGAAAGAGAACUGCCUUAGCCAUGAUUUCGUUAGUAGACCUAUUUAUGAUUCAAUUGCAAUUUUCAGAUAGGAUGUGAACAUGGAAUUUCAUUGAAAAUAGUUUAAUUUUUUAUAUAAAAGGUUUUGUAUAUAAUGUGUGUCAGUGACUAUUUUCAAAAUCAUUUUCAUCAAGACACCUUUUUUCUAAAAUAGGCAUUGCAUACACAUAUGCACACGUAUGUGCAUGUGCCACACAUUUUUUGUAUAAUGUUGGGUUUGAUUAUAAAAGUGUUGUCAAAUGUUUUAUUUAUCUGCAUAUAGCAGUGGUUGGCUUUUUUGAAUUGAAAUUUUUGCGCAUUGAUGCAUUGAAAUAAGGAAAAUUAUUUAUCUCUGAGCACUAAACUUAUUUUUGCAUAUUUCUGUAAUAUUGCAGUCCCCAGAUCCAGAACAUGGGAAGUUAGGGAAAAUGUGUGAUUUUGUGUUUUGAAUUACUGUCAGAAUUACAUACACAAUUACAACAAACUUUUUUUAAAAGACAUUUCAUUGUACUGCAAAAAUCUGAAUAUUUAUAUUUCUUGUUUUUUUCUUUAUAUGUUUUGCAUUUUAAUAUGUUGAGCCACUGGAAAUUUGUAACAGAUUAAUUUGUUAUAGGAGUUUAAAUGUGUUGUCAUUGUCUCCAUUGUCUUUGUCCAGAGCCUAUUAUUAUGGAAACAAUAAAAUUUAUUGUGUCAGUUGCUUUGAUUCUU